CUGUUCCCCGCCCGCGGCAAACAUGGCGGUGGACUCGGCGAUGGAGCUGUUAUUUUUAGAUACUUUUAAACACCCGAGCGCUGAGGUAAUACAUGUAUGAGGUACAAAUACAAAAGGUACAAAAGAGUAUGUGGUAAAAACAAAGUUCUCAUAUAGAUGUGGUUCGUUUUCCAUGUGUGGUUUAUAUCAAUGAAGUCCGAGUCAUACCCCCAGGAGUAAGAGCCCAUAGCAGUCUGCCAGACAAUAGAGCAUAUGGAGAGACAUCUCCCCAUACAUUUCAAUUAGACUUAUUCUUCAACAAUGUAAGCAAACCAAGUGCCCCUGUUUUCGAUAGGUUGGGAAGCCUGGAAUAUGAUGAGAAUACUUCCAUCAUCUUUAGACCUAACUCAAAGGUGAAUACUGAUGGUCUGGUGCUAAGAGGCUGGUAUAACUGUCUGACACUGGCAAUAUAUGGAUCAGUGGAUAGAGUGAUAAGUCAUGACAGAGACUCUCCACCACCACCACCUCCACCGCCACCACCUCCCCAGCCACAACCAAGUUUGAAAAGGAAUCCAAAACAUGCUGAUGGGGAGAAAGAAGAUCAGUUUAAUGGAAGCCCUCCAAGACCACAGCCAAGGGGACCAAGAACUCCUCCAGGACCCCCUCCACCUGAUGAUGAUGAAGAUGAUCCUGUGCCUCUGCCAGUGUCUGGUGACAAGGAAGAGGAUGCUCCUCAUAGAGAAGAUUACUUUGAGCCCAUUUCUCCUGAUCGGAAUUCUGUUCCCCAGGAAGGGCAAUAUUCUGAUGAAGGAGAAGUAGAAGAGGAACAACAAGAAGAAGGAGAAGAAGAUGAAGAUGAUGUGGAUGUAGAGGAAGAAGAGGAUGAGGAUGAGGAUGAUCGACGAACAGUAGACAGUAUUCCUGAGGAGGAAGAGGAAGAUGAAGAGGAAGAAGGUGAAGAGGAUGAAGAAGGUGAAGGGGAUGAUGGUUAUGAACAAAUUUCCAGUGAUGAAGAUGGAAUUGCUGACUUGGAACGUGAAACAUUUAAGUAUCCAAACUUUGAUGUUGAAUACACUGCUGAAGACUUAGCUUCAGUUCCUCCUAUGACAUAUGAUCCAUAUGACAGGGAGCUUGUACCACUCUUAUACUUCAGUUGUCCAUACAAGACUACUUUUGAAAUUGAAAUCAGUAGAAUGAAGGAUCAAGGUCCAGAUAAAGAAAAUUCAGGGGCAAUCGAAGCCUCAGUGAAGUUAACAGAACUCUUAGAUUUGUAUAGAGAAGAUAGAGGUGCAAAAUGGGUAACAGCUUUAGAAGAAAUUCCAAGUUUAAUAAUAAAAGGGUUAAGCUAUUUGCAAUUGAAAAACACAAAACAAGACUCCCUUGGCCAGUUGGUAGACUGGACCAUGCAAGCUUUAAAUUUACAAGUAGCGCUUCGCCAACCUAUCGCCUUAAAUGUUCGACAGCUCAAAGCUGGGACCAAAUUAGUGUCCUCACUAGCAGAAUGUGGGGCUCAAGGAGUUACAGGACUGCUACAAGCAGGAGUGAUCAGUGGAUUAUUUGAACUUCUGUUUGCUGAUCACGUAUCAUCUUCUCUUAAGUUAAAUGCUUUUAAAGCUUUGGACAGUGUCAUUAGUAUGACAGAAGGAAUGGAAGCUUUUUUAAGAGGUAGGCAGAAUGAAAAAAGUGGUUAUCAAAAGCUUCUGGAACUCAUACUUUUAGAUCAGACUGUGAGGGUUGUUACUGCUGGUUCAGCUAUUCUCCAAAAAUGCCAUUUCUAUGAAGUCUUGUCAGAGAUUAAAAGACUUGGUGACCAUUUAGCAGAGAAGACUUCAUCUCUUCCUAACCACAGUGAACCUGAUCACGACACAGAUGCUGGACUUGAGAGAACAAACCCAGAAUAUGAAAAUGAGGUGGAAGCUUCUAUGGAUAUGGAUCUUUUGGAAUCCUCAAAUAUAAGUGAAGGGGAAAUAGAAAGGCUUAUUAACCUCCUAGAAGAAGUUUUUCAUUUAAUGGAAACUGCCCCUCAUACAAUGAUCCAACAACCUGUUAAGUCUUUCCCAACGAUGGCACGAAUUACUGGACCUCCAGAGAGGGAUGAUCCAUACCCUGUUCUCUUUAGAUAUCUUCACAGUCAUCACUUCUUGGAGUUGGUUACCUUGCUUCUGUCAAUUCCAGUAACAAGUGCUCACCCUGGUGUGCUGCAAGCCACAAAAGAUGUUUUGAAGUUUCUUGCACAGUCACAGAAGGGUCUUCUUUUUUUUAUGUCGGAAUAUGAAGCAACAAAUUUAUUGAUCCGAGCUCUGUGUCACUUUUAUGAUCAAGAUGAGGAGGAAGGUCUCCAAUCUGAUGGUGUUAUUGAUGAUGCAUUUGCCUUGUGGCUACAGGACUCAACACAGACAUUGCAAUGUAUUACAGAACUGUUCAGCCAUUUUCAGCGUUGUACAGCCAGUGAAGAAACAGACCAUUCAGAUCUCUUGGGAACCCUGCACAAUCUUUAUUUGAUUACUUUUAAUCCUGUGGGAAGAUCAGCUGUUGGCCAUGUUUUUAGUCUGGAGAAAAAUCUCCAAAGUCUUAUUACUCUAAUGGAGUACUAUUCCAAAGAAGCCUUGGGUGAUUCCAAAUCUAAGAAGUCAGUAGCUUAUAAUUACGCAUGCAUACUUAUUUUGGUGGUGGUUCAGUCUUCCAGUGAUGUUCAAAUGCUAGAACAACAUGCAGCAUCUCUCUUGAAGCUUUGUAAAGCAGAUGAAAAUAAUGCUAAAUUGCAAGAACUUGGCAAGUGGCUUGAACCUCUGAAAAACCUUAGAUUUGAAAUUAACUGCAUCCCAAACUUAAUUGAGUAUGUUAAGCAGAAUAUCGAUAACUUGAUGACCCCAGAAGGAGUUGGCCUUACCACUGCCUUACGUGUUCUCUGUAAUGUUGCAUGCCCACCACCUCCUGUUGAAGGUCAACAGAAAGAUCUGAAAUGGAAUCUUGCCGUUAUUCAGCUUUUUUCUGCUGAAGGAAUGGACACGUUUAUUCGAGUUCUGCAAAAAUUGAACAGUAUUCUGACUCAGCCUUGGAGGCUCCAUGUCAACAUGGGGACUACCCUUCACAGAGUUACUACUAUUUCAAUGGCUCGCUGCACACUCACUCUUCUUAAAACUAUGUUAACGGAACUCCUGAGAGGUGGAUCCUUUGAGUUUAAGGACAUGCGUGUUCCUUCAGCGCUUGUUACUUUACAUAUGCUCCUGUGCUCUAUCCCCCUCUCAGGUCGUUUGGAUAGUGAUGAACAGAAAAUUCAGAAUGAUAUCAUUGAUAUUUUACUGACUUUUACACAAGGAGUUAAUGAAAAACUCACAAUCUCAGAAGAGACUCUGGCCAAUAAUACUUGGUCUUUAAUGUUAAAAGAAGUUCUUUCUUCAAUCUUGAAGGUUCCUGAAGGAUUUUUUUCUGGACUCAUACUCCUUUCAGAGCUGCUGCCUCUUCCAUUGCCCAUGCAAACAACUCAGGUUAUUGAGCCACAUGAUAUAUCAGUGGCACUCAACACCCGAAAAUUGUGGAGCAUGCACCUUCAUGUUCAAGCAAAGUUGCUCCAAGAAAUAGUUCGCUCUUUCUCUGGCACAACCUGCCAGCCCAUUCAACAUAUGUUACGGCGUAUUUGUGUUCAAUUGUGUGACCUUGCCUCACCAACUGCACUUCUGAUUAUGAGAACUGUGUUGGAUUUGAUUGUAGAAGACUUGCAAAGCACUUCAGAAGAUAAAGAAAAACAGUAUACUAGCCAAACCACCAGGUUGCUUGCUCUUCUUGAUGCUCUGGCUUCACACAAAGCUUGUAAAUUAGCUAUUUUGCAUCUAAUUAAUGGAACUAUUAAAGGUGAUGAAAGAUAUGCAGAGAUAUUCCAGGAUCUUUUAGCUUUGGUGCGGUCUCCUGGAGACAGUGUUAUUCGCCAACAGUGUGUUGAAUAUGUCACAUCCAUUUUGCAGUCUCUCUGUGAUCAGGACAUUGCACUUAUCUUACCAAGCUCUUCUGAAGGUUCUAUUUCUGAACUGGAGCAGCUCUCCAAUUCUCUACCAAAUAAAGAAUUGAUGACCUCAAUCUGUGACUGUCUGUUGGCUACGCUAGCUAACUCUGAGAGCAGUUACAACUGUUUACUGACAUGUGUCAGAACAAUGAUGUUUCUUGCAGAGCAUGAUUAUGGAUUAUUUCAUUUAAAAAGUUCUUUAAGGAAAAACAGUAGUGCUCUGCAUAGUUUACUGAAACGAGUGGUCAGCACAUUUAGUAAGGACACAGGAGAGCUUGCAUCUUCAUUUUUAGAAUUUAUGAGACAAAUUCUUAACUCUGACACAAUUGGAUGCUGUGGAGAUGAUAAUGGUCUCAUGGAAGUAGAGGGAGCUCAUACAUCACGGACGAUGAGUAUUAAUGCUGCAGAGUUAAAACAGCUUCUACAAAGCAAAGAAGAAAGUCCAGAAAAUUUGUUCCUUGAACUAGAGAAGCUUGUUUUGGAACAUUCAAAAGAUGAUGACAAUCUGGAUUCUUUGUUGGACAGUGUAGUUGGACUUAAGCAGAUGCUGGAGUCAUCAGGUGACCCUUUACCUCUCAGUGACCAGGAUGUAGAACCAGUACUUUCAGCUCCAGAAUCUCUUCAGAAUCUGUUUAACAAUAGGACUGCCUAUGUGCUUGCUGAUGUCAUGGAUGAUCAGUUGAAAUCUAUGUGGUUCACUCCAUUUCAGGCUGAAGAGAUAGAUACAGAUCUGGAUUUGGUAAAGGUUGACUUAAUUGAACUCUCUGAAAAAUGCUGUAGUGACUUUGAUUUGCACUCAGAAUUAGAGCGCUCAUUUUUGUCAGAACCAUCAUCUCCAGGAAGAACCAAGACUACUAAAGGAUUCAAACUUGGGAAGCACAAGCAUGAGACCUUUAUAACGUCAAGUGGAAAAUCUGAAUACAUUGAACCUGCCAAAAGAGCUCAUGUUGUGCCACCACCAAGAGGAAGGGGCAGGGGAGGAUUUGGACAGGGUAUACGACCUCAUGAUAUUUUUCGUCAGAGAAAACAGAACACAAGUAGACCACCAUCUAUGCAUGUGGAUGACUUUGUUGCUGCUGAAAGUAAAGAAGUGGUUCCUCAAGAUGGAAUACCUCCACCAAAACGGCCACUCAAAGUAUCACAGAAGAUUUCUUCCCGUGGUGGGUUUUCAGGCAAUAGAGGAGGACGGGGUGCUUUCCACAGUCAGAAUAGGUUUUUCACACCACCUGCUUCAAAAGGAAACUACAGUCGUCGGGAAGGAACAAGAGGCUCCAGUUGGAGUGCUCAGAAUACUCCUCGAGGAAAUUACAAUGAAAGUCGUGGAGGCCAGAGCAAUUUUAACAGAGGCCCUCUUCCACCAUUACGACCCCUUAGUUCUACAGGUUACCGCCCAAGUCCUCGGGACCGUGCUUCUAGAGGUCGUGGGGGACUUGGACCUUCCUGGGCUAGUGCAAAUAGCGGCAGUGGAGGCUCAAGAGGAAAGUUUGUUAGUGGAGGCAGUGGUAGAGGUCGUCAUGUACGCUCCUUUACACGAUAAAAAUCCUUUUGGGAACAUCUUAACUGUAUAUGAACAUUUCACGAGGACAAUAAAAAUAAGACAUUGAAGGACCAAUUUAGACUUAGCAGUUAUCUGGAGACAUCUGAGAGAAUAUUUUUAUCUGAAGAAAGCAGAAUUUGUUUGAUACCUAACAAGAUUUCAAUAAAAAUCCAAACUUUGUAUGUACGUUUGUAUAUAUUUUCCCUUUUUUGUAUGACUAUUUAUUUAGAAAAUUUCUAGGUGAAAAACUAAAUGAUGUUUUGUAUUUUUCUUGCCUAUAGCACAGAUAUUCUCAAACUUUCUCAGCUCAUGACACUAUUUAGUGCCUCAGUACUUUUUUCACAGCAUACCUGGUCCAAAAGAAAUAUCUAAUACUUGUGUUUAUUAAGCAGUUAGAUCCAACAGCUUAAUAAGAAUGUACAUCAUCACCACUAGUAACUGUGGACACUGCAUGUCUCAAACCUUGGAAUCAGUAUCAUUUUCUUUUCCUCUCUGCUUCUUGCACAGUACUUUUUAUCAAACUGCUGAAAACCCAGUUUUGUAAAGAUAUGUUGUUAUAGAAAGGAAUAUAAUGCUAUUUAAUGUUGAAAAUGUAAACUACCUCAAAGUAGUAGUUUAUGUGAUGUCCAACAGGUGUUGCUAUGUUUUUCUCAAAAAUUUUAAAAUAUUGUGUGGCACCCAUGUUAAUUUGCUAAGGUGCCCUGCUACACAGUUUGGGAACCAUGGCUGUACCAAAAGAAACAAAAUACUCCUCUCCUUUGUAUUAGAAAUCUGAACUUUGCAUUUCAGCUUUGGACCUACUGACACUAUUUUAUUAUACAAAUUAUUUAAAGCCUAAAAUAAGGAAUAUCCUAAUACUAUUAUUUUGGGAAUCAGAAACAUCUAAUAAAGCUGGACUUUAUACAUAGAAAUAAAGCUUACAACUUUGAGAAAGUAGCCAUAUUUUCCCCAAGAUACGUCUUAACACACUGAGUCUAUAUAAGUGGCGUAAAAUACAGAGUUAUCUUAAUCAGAAAA